ACUCUGUCACCUACGCUAUGCCCUGCUGUAGUCACAGGAGGUGUAGAGAGGACCCCGGGACAUCUGAAAGCCAGGAAAUGGUGCGUGUCUGGGGCCGGGUGUCGUGAGACGGGGGAGGGGCUGCCUGGACCGACCGGAACCGACUGUGGCGAGACCCUGGCUUUCCUGCGGGCGACUUUGGGAUCUGGGACCGAGUCCUCCUGGAGCCGCUCGGCCCUCGGUCCCCUCGACUGCUCGGUGUGGCUGGGCCGGUAGCCGGGACACCAGGCGUCCUGUCUCGUCUCUGCGCGGCGACUGCGGUUCCAGAGCCCUCUAUGGGCAGCUCCGCGCCCGCAGCCACGCGUCUACCCAGAUUGUGCGGGGGCCACGGGAGGGUCAUGUGGGUGAUCCCGACUCGGGUGUGGGGUUCGUGCUUGGGAGGAGCAGCGGUCUGUGGGGCCCCCAGUGUCCACUUUUUCUCCUGUUAAAAAUUAAACUGAGGAACGUUAACAAAGAGUUCAUUUGAGCAAACAGCGAUUCACGAAUGAGACACACCCAGUCCUGGCUUGUGGUUUGUCAACGGAAAAAGCCAAACUAUGUAAAAUAAAGAAGUUUAUUCGGAGCCGAAUAGGAGAGACCUUGGCCGAGGGAAAAACAACCCCAAGAAGCCUGGAGAGGAGUGGGCUUUGCUGGAUAUUUCCCAGAGGAAACUCUACAAGGAAGUGAUGCUGGAAACUUUCAGGAACCUGACCUCUGUAGGAAAAAGUUGGAAAGACCAGAACAUUGAAUAUGAGUACCAAAACCCCAGGAGAAACUUCAGGAGUCUCAUAGAAAAGAAAGUCAAUGAAAUUAAAGAUGACAGUCAUUGUGGAGAAACUUUUACCCAGGUUCCAGAUGACAGGCUGAACUUCCAGGAGAAGAAAGCUUCUCCUGAAAUAAAAUCAUGUGACAGCUUUGUGUGUGGAGAAGUUGGCCUAGGUAACUCAUCUUUUAAUAUGAACAUCAGAGGUGACAUUGGACACAAGGCCUAUGAGUAUCAGGAAUAUGGACCGAAGCCAUGUAAGUGUCAACAACCUAAAAAAGCCUUCAGAUAUCACCCCUCCUUUAGAACACCACAAAGGGAUCACACUGGAGAGAAACCCUAUGCUUGUAAAGAAUGUGGAAAAACUUUUAUUUCCCAUUCAAGCAUUCAAAGACACGUGGUAAUGCACAGUGGGGAUGGACCUUAUAAAUGUAAAUUUUGUGGGAAAGCCUUCCAUUGUCUCAGUUUAUAUCUUAUCCAUGAAAGAAUUCACACUGGAGAGAAACCAUAUGAAUGUAAACAAUGUGGUAAAUCCUUUAGUUAUUCUGCUACCCUUCGAAUACACGAAAGAACUCACACUGGAGAAAAGCCUUAUGAAUGUCAGCAAUGUGGGAAAGCAUUUCAUAGUCCCAGAUGCUAUCGUAGACAUGAAAGGAUUCACACGGGAGAGAAGGCUUAUCAAUGUAAGGAAUGUGGAAAAGCAUUCACGUGUCCCCAGUAUGUUCGUAUACAUGAAAGGACCCACUCUAGGAAAAAACCCUAUGAAUGUACGCAGUGUGGGAAAGCAUUAUCCUCUCUUACAAGUUUUCAAACACACAUAAGAAUGCACUCUGGAGAAAGACCUUAUGAAUGUAAGAUAUGUGGGAAAGGCUUUUGUUCUGCCAAUUCAUUUCAAAGACAUGAAAAAACUCACAGUGGAGAGAAACCCUAUAAAUGCAAGCAAUGUGGUAAAGCCUUCAUUCAUUCCAGUUCCCUUCGUUAUCAUGAAAGGAUUCACACUGGAGAGAAACCCUAUGAGUGUAAGCAAUGUGGGAAGGCCUUCAGAUCUUCCUCACACCUUCAAUUGCAUGGUAGGACUCACACUGGAGAGAAGCCCUAUGAAUGUCAGGAAUGUGGGAAAGCCUUCAGAUCUAUGAAGAACCUUCAAAGUCAUGAAAGGACACAAACACACGUAAGAAUACACUCUGGAGAAAGACCUUAUAAAUGUAAGCUAUGUGGGAAAGGCUUUUAUUGUCCCAAAUCAUUGCAAAGACAUGAAAAAACUCACACUGGAGAGAAACUCUAUGAAUGCAAGCAAUGUGGUGAAGCCUUCAGUAGUUCCAGUUCCUUUCGAUACCAUGAAAGGACUCACACUGGAGAGAAACCCUAUAAAUGCAAGCAAUGUGGGAAAGCCUUCAGAGCUGCCUCAGUCCUUCGAAUGCAUGGUAGGACUCACCCUGAAGAUAAACCCUAUGAGUGUAAGCAAUGAGGGAAAGCCUUCAGAUCUGCCUCACACCUUUGAAUGCAUGGUAGGACACACAAUCAAGAGAAACCAUGAAUGUAAAGAAUGUGGGAAACCCUUCAGGUCUGCCCAGAACCUUCGAAUUCAGUAAAGGACACAAGCACACAUAAGAAUGCAUUCUGGAUAGCUGAACAAAAGGCAGCAGAAACUUCUGCAGACUUAAAUGUCCCUGUCUGACAGCUUUGAAGAGAGUAGCAGUCCUCCCAGCAUGGAGUUUGAGAUCUAAGAAUGGACAGUCUGCCUCCUCAAGUGGGUCCCUGAUCUCCAAGUAGCCUAACUGGGAGGCACUUCCCAGUAGGGGCCAACUGACACCUCAUACGGCCGUGUGCCCCUCUGUGACGAAGCUUCCAGAGGAAGGAUCAGGCAACAACAUUUGCCGUUCUGCAAUAUUUGCUGUUCUGCAGCCCCUGCUGGUGAUACCCAGGCAAACAGGGUCUGGAGUGGACCUCAAGCAAAAUCCAACAGACCUCAGCUGAGGGUCCUGACUGUUAGAAGGAAAACUAACAAACAGAAAGGACAACCACACCAAAACCCAUCUGUACAUCACCAUCAUCAAAGACCAAAA